GGGGACGGGAGUGGCGAGCUUCAGGUCCACCGGCUGCCACCGAGUGAUGGGACCGGAGGACAGGAGAGGUCGCUCAGCCAAGAGCCCCGGGGAGGCGGUGCCUUCUCGGUGGGGUCAGCAACGGUCUCUGGGGGGUGCCUGGGAGCGGCAGCCGGUCUCCGCCUUGGCGGCCCACAGCCACCGCGGACGCCUCCCUCCCGGAUGUCUCCUCGCUGCCCUUCCCUGGCCGAAGCCCUCCCCUGCAGCCUCCUCCCCACCUGCCGGCCCUGUGUUCUCACUGCUCUUCUCUGCUCUGGGAUCCGCAGGAUGACGUCUGUCCUGCUUCUUCACUGUCCUUUACAGUCACCAGUCUCGGCCGGGCGCAGUGGCUCACGCCUGUAAUCCCAGCACUUUGGGAGGCCAAGGCGGUCGGAUCCUUGGAGAUCAGGAGUUCGAGACCAGUCUGGCAAACGUGGUGAAAACCGGUCUCUACUAAAAAUACAGAAAUUAGCCGGGCAUGGUGGCCCACGCCUGUAAUAAUGUCAGCUAUGUGCUGAGGCAGGAAAAUCACUUCAACUCGGGAGGCAGAGGUUGCAGUGAGCUGGGAUUGCGCCACUGCACUCCAGCCUGGCAGACAGAGUGAGACUUCGUCUCAAAACAAAAAAAAGAAAAACACAAAAAAACCACCACCAACAACAACAAAAAAAUAAAGCCACCAGUCUCGGAGUUUCAAAUCUGAGCACUCUUAUCCAUCUUAAUUCUUUCAAUAAUUCAGCUAAACGAAUGGGGUCCUGAGAAUCUGCAGAGCCAGGCUCAGCGCUCGCCUGCAGAGCCUGCGGUCUGUGGGGACCACCAGCAAGAUGAGGAAUCACCUUCGGGAGGAAGGGUCGUGCUGGGGAGGGUCGCGCCGGCGGGGUCAAGAGAACCUCCUCCAGGGUGGGAAUCAGAGCCUCCGGGCCGCGGUGUUUGAGGGCCCUGCAUCAUGGAAACUCUUUCUAAUGCAAGUGGUACUUUUGCCAUACGCCUUUUAAAGAUACUGUGUCAAGAUAACCCUUCGCACAACGUGUUCUGUUCUCCUGUGAGCAUCUCCUCUGCCCUGGCCAUGGUUCUCCUAGGGGCAAAGGGAAACACCGCAACCCAGAUGGCCCAGGCACUGUCUUUAAACACAGAGGAAGACAUUCAUCGGGCUUUCCAGUCGCUUCUCACUGAAGUGAACAAGGCUGGCACACAGUACCUGCUGAGAACGGCCAACAGGCUCUUUGGAGAGAAAACUUGUCAGUUCCUCUCAACGUUUAAGGAAUCCUGUCUUCAAUUCUACCAUGCUGAGCUGAAGGAGCUUUCCUUUAUCAGAGCUGCAGAAGAGUCCAGGAAACACAUCAACACCUGGGUCUCAAAAAAGACCGAAGGUAAAAUUGAAGAGUUGUUGCCGGGUAGCUCAAUUGAUGCAGAAACCAGGCUGGUUCUUGUCAAUGCCAUCUACUUCAAAGGAAAGUGGAAUGAACCGUUUGACGAAACAUACACAAGGGAAAUGCCCUUUAAAAUAAACCAGGAGGAGCAAAGGCCAGUGCAGAUGAUGUAUCAGGAGGCCACGUUUAAGCUCGCCCACGUGGGCGAGGUGCGCGCGCAGCUGCUGGAGCUGCCCUACGCCAGGAAGGAGCUGAGCCUGCUGGUGCUGCUGCCUGACGACGGCGUGGAGCUCAGCACGGUGGAAAAAAGUCUCACUUUUGAGAAACUCACAGCCUGGACCAAGCCAGACUGUAUGAAGAGUACUGAGGUUGAAGUUCUCCUUCCAAAAUUUAAACUACAAGAGGAUUAUGACAUGGAAUCUGUGCUUCGGCAUUUGGGAAUUGUUGAUGCCUUCCAACAGGGCAAGGCUGACUUGUCGGCAAUGUCAGCGGAGAGAGACCUGUGUCUGUCCAAGUUCGUGCACAAGAGUUUUGUGGAGGUGAAUGAAGAAGGCACCGAGGCAGCGGCAGCGUCGAGCUGCUUUGUAGUUGCAGAGUGCUGCAUGGAAUCUGGCCCCAGGUUCUGUGCUGACCACCCUUUCCUUUUCUUCAUCAGGCACAACAGAGCCAACAGCAUUCUGUUCUGUGGCAGGUUCUCAUCGCCAUAAAGGGUGCACUUACCGUGCACUCGGCCAUUUCCCUCUUCCUGUGUCCCCAGAUCCCCACUACAGCUCCAAGAGGAUGGGCCUAGAAAGCCAAGUGCAAAGAUGAGGGCAGAUUCUUUACCUGUCUGCCCUCAUGAUUUGCCAGCAUGAAUUCAUGAUGCUCCACACUCGCUUAUGCUACUUAAUCAGAAUCUUGAGAAAAUAGACCAUAAUGAUUCCCUGUUGUAUUAAAAUUGCAGUCCAAAUCCCAUAGGAUGGCAAGCAAAGUUCUUCUAGAAUUCCACAUGCAAUUCACUCUGGCGACCCUGUGCUUUCCUGACACUGCGAAUACAUUCCUUAACCCGCUGCCUCAGUGGUAAUAAAUGGUGCUAGAUAUUGCUACUAUUUUAUAGAUUUCCUGGUGCUUAGCCUUAUAAAAAAGGUUGUAAAAUGUACAUUUAUAUUUUAUCUUUUUUUUUUUUUUUUUUCUGAGACGCAGUCUGGCUCUCUGUCGCCCAGGCUGGAGUGCAGUGGCUCGAUCUCGGCUCACUGCAAGCUCCGCCUCCCGGGUUCACGCCAUUCUCCUGCCUCAGCCUCCCGAGUAGCUGGGACUACAGGCGCCCGCCACCACGCCCGGCUAAUUUUUUGUAUUUUUAGUAGAGACGGGGUUUCACCGUGUUAGCCAGGAUGGUGUCGAUCUCCUGACCUCGUGAUCCACCCGCCUCGGCCUCCCAAAGUGCUGGGAUUACAGGCUUGAGCCACCGCGCCCGGCUAUAUUUUAUCUUUUAUCUUUUUCUUUGACAUUUACCAAUCACCAAGCAUGCACCAAACACUGCUUUAGGCACUGGGGACACAAAGGGGACAGAGCCAUCCUCCUUUGACACCUGGUCUUCAGUUCUGUGCCCAACGUAUAUAGUUUUGACAAUGACCAGGUUGGACUGUUUAAUGUCUUUCAACUUACCACGUAAUCCUCUUGUAGGGAUCACAUCUUUCUUUAUGAUAUUGUAUUUCUCUACCUCUAACAGUAAAAAUUCCAUUCAACCCUUAAAGCUCACUUCAAAUUCUUCUUUGAGAAGUUUUUCCUUUCUCCGCAACCAGAUGUACAUAUUUGAACUCUCUUUGUACUUGGAGGGCACUUCUUUCGUGGUAGUUCUUUUAUUUUUAUUAAUCUCUGUAUCCUUAGAUAGUCCUCCAACAACCAAAGGUUGGGACUCUGUCUUACAUAUCUGGGUGCCCCUCAUAGUGCAGUAAUAAGUAAGUUGAUUAUAUACGAGCUAUGUAACUUAUAUUUUUUAAUGGUUGGAUAUCACUGAGUUUUUUUUUUUAAGAAUUUUUUUAUUGAGGUAAACUUCACAUAACAUAAAAUUAACUAUUUUAAAGUGAGAAGUUCAGUGCCACUUAGUAUUGUUAACAAUGUUGCAUAACCACCACCUUUAUUUAAAGUUCCAAAAAAAAUGUUCUCCUCUAAAAGGAAACCCCAUCCCAUUAAGCAGAUACUCUCCAUUCCUUCCUUCCUCCAGCCCCCAGCAACCACCAAUCUGCUUUCUGUCUCUAUGGAUUUAUCUAUUCUUGCUAUUUUAUAUAAAUUGAAUUGUAUGAGACCUUUUGUGUCUGGCUUCUUUCACUUAGUACAAGUUUUUGAGAUUUAUUUACAUAGUAGCAUGUAUCAACACUUCAUUUUUAUGGCCAAAUAAAAUUGUAUUAUGUGUUUAUAGCACAAUUUAUUUAUCCACUCAUUCAUUGAUGGACUUUGGGUUGUUUCUGACUUUUGGCUAUUGGGAAUAGUGCUGCUAUGAAUGUUUGUGUACCUGUAUUUGUUUGAAUGCCUAUUUUGCAUUCUCUUGGGUAUAUAUCUAGGAGUGGAACUGCUGGGUCAUAUGUUAAUUCUAUGUUUAGCUUUUUGAGGAACAGACAAACUGUUUUCCACAGCAGUUGAACCAUUCCACAUUCCCACCAGCAAUGUAUGAGAAUUCCAAUUUCUGUCCACUUCCUCACCAACACUUAUUAUUUUCCUUUUCCUUUUUUUAAAAAAAAUAAGUUAUGGCCAUCUUAGUGGGUGUGAAGUGGUAUCUCAUUGUGUUUUUUAUUUGCAUUUCCUAUGUAAUGAGCUAGAAACUAAAGUACAAACUAGAUGGGACAUCCAGUCCCUUUGAUAGAUAAUGCUGAGUAAAAAAUGAGAUGAAAGACAUUUGUUUGUUUUUAGAACACGAGUGACAGUUUGUUAAAAAGCUUUAGAGGAGGAAUGAAAACAAAGUGAAGUACACUUAGAAAAGGGCCAAGUGGACAUCUUGGAUGUCAAGUGCCUAGUUCAGUAUCUUUUUUUUUUUUUUUUUUUUUUUUGAGACAGUGCCUCACUCUGUCACCCAGGCUGGAGUGUAGUGGCAUGAUCUGGGCUCACUGCAACCUCCUCCUCCUGGAUUCAAGCAAUUCUCUUGCUUCAGCCUCCCAAGUAGCUGAGACUACAAGCACCCACCAUCACACCCAGCUAAUUUUGUAUUUUUCAGUAGAGACGGGGUUUCGCCACAUUGGCCGUGUUGGUCUUGAACUCCUGGCCUCAAGCGAUCCGCCUACCUCAGCCUCCCAAAGUGCUAGGAUUACAGGCAUAAGCCACUGAGCCCAGCCCUAGUUCAGUAUCUUUUAUGUAAAUUACAAACAUCUGCAACAUUAUGUAUCAUAUGCAGAUACUUAUUGCAUUUCUUUUAUUAGUGGUGAAAGUGUUCUAUGCAUUUAUUGGCUCUUGAAUUUCCUCAUCUAUGAAUUGUCAUUCAUACACCUACUUUUCUGCUUCGUUUUUACAUAUGUCUUUGCCUAUUAAAGAUAUUAUCCCUCUGUUUUAUAUUUUCUCUCAUUCUUGUAUUGCCUUUUAAAUUUUGUUAUGAUGUUUCAUUAAUAAACAGUGUUUUGUUUUCCUCUAUAA